UUUUGUCGCCAAAAGUGACCUUGAGGAACCCUGGGAGCUCAGGAAGGAAGGAGCGCCCAGAAGCAGGGACAGGGAGCUGGUUGGGGAGGACCAGAAAUCAGGUUAUCAAUACUCUGGCUGACCAUCGUCAUCGUGGGACUGACUUUGGUGGAAGUCCUUGGUUACUUAUCAUUACUGUGUUUCUGAGAAGUUAUAAAUUUGCCAUCUCCCUCUGCACAAGUUACCUUUGUGUGUCUUUCCUGAAGACUAUCUUCCCGUCUCAAAAUGGACAUGAUGGAUCCACGGAUGUACAGCAGAGAGCCAGGAGGUCCAACCGCCGUAGACAGGAAGGAAUUAAAAUUGUCCUGGAAGACAUCUUUACUUUAUGGAGACAGGUGGAAACCAAAGUUCGAGCUAAAAUCCGUAAGAUGAAGGUGACAACAAAAGUCAACCGUCAUGACAAAAUCAAUGGAAAGAGGAAGACCGCCAAAGAACAUCUGAGGAAACUAAGCAUGAAAGAACGUGAGCACGGAGAAAAGGAGAGGCAGGUGUCAGAGGCAGAGGAAAAUGGGAAAUUGGAUAUGAAAGAAAUACACACCUACAUGGAAAUGUUUCAACGUGCGCAAGCGUUGCGGCGGCGGGCAGAGGACUACUACAGAUGCAAAAUCACCCCUUCUGCAAGAAAGCCUCUUUGCAACCGGGUAAGUUUGCUUGUUUUCCUUGCUUUUGGACAUAGUCUGCCAGGUCAGGACAUGGAUACAUUUUUCUCCCUACGGCUCUGUGCUCAAGCCCUGCAGAGGGAGAUGGCAGAGAGGAAGGCUGCCUACAAGCAUCACAGUCCCAUCCCUGUUGGUAACCGUGUUGCGCAAAAACACCUUCAUCCCCACCCAGUGGGGCCCCCAUCUAAUAUUCUAAGUGUCAGAGGUUCCGUAUUUGUAAUAGCAAAUGGGCCCUGACUGUAAAUUAGUGAAGAGUGAAUGUAACUUAUUACCCACAGGGACAAUUCCAAAUGAGGGCCUUAAAUGAUGCUCAGCUAAGCUGGUUCUUGUGUGGCCUCUGUACCUUCAAAAGCUGCCGAGUCCUAUGAUUGCACGCGAUGGGACUUGUACACUUGAAGUGAAACACAGUUUUAAAACUUGCUUUGUUUAGAAUUCCCACCUCAUUUUUCCAUGGACAAAAGUAUUCUUUAUGUCCUAGUGCACUUACAAUUUGGUAUUACCUGGGAGUGAAAAGAAAUAUUACAGCCAUGCCUAACUGACUUCUUGAGGUAAGAUUGUUCUGUCAGAAAACCCUCUCCCAGUUCCCCUGCAGCUCUUCAGGAAUCCACAUCUCUCCAGAGCUCUUUGUUCUCAUGGGUGGCACCUCCAGAGUGAAGAAGAUCCUUUGUCAAGAAGGGAAACAGAGGGGAAAUGAGAGGGUCCUGCAGGCAGAGCUGGAAUCAACUUCCACUCUGCCUCUUGCAAGCUGUGUGACCCUGGGCACAAUUUCUCCUUCCUCUGGAAACCUCUGUUUUCUUAGAUUUGGAGCAGGAUGGUCACACUGACCUUGCAGAGUUCUGAGAAUCAGAGACAGAACAUAAAAGGCCUGGAAAACAUUCUCCAAAAAGAAGCUGCAACAUGUGUGGACAAUGGGCUUUUCAUGCCUCUCUUACUGUCUCUUACUGUCUAUUGACCUGGUGCAAGAAACAUGCUCUGGUGAUGGCUGUGAGGGAGGAAUGAGGAUAGACAUAGACACUCCUGUGUCUCAAACAUGCUUCUUUAUUACUCUGUUAUGACUCUGUCUUCCCUGGGGCAGGACCCCAGCCUGCCUACAUUUGCAGACAGACACAGUGGCAUGUGGAGACAACAGUGUGUCCCAAAGACUUUUCUUUACCCCCUAGCUGUCGGCAGUACUCAGUGGAAGGGUGAUAUUAUGACACUGACACUGCUAUUUUGAAACCUGGAGGAUGGAAAGGUGCAAAAAUCUAUCACCAGCAACAGAAGGUGCAGACUGUGUUGGUGGCGGUAAUUUUGUCCAUCAAAUGAAUAUGUGUGAAAACAUUCCCUCCUUUGGCCCUACAGGUCAGAAUGGCGGCAGUGGAGCAUCGUCAUUCUUCAGGAUUGCCCUACUGGCCCUACCUCACAGCUGAAACUUUAAAAAACAGGAUGGGCCACCAGCCACCUCCUCCAACUCAACAACAUUCUAUAAUUGAUAACUCCCUGAGCCUCAAGACACCUUCCGAGUGUCUGCUCACUCCCCUUCCACCCUCAGCUCUACCCUCAGCGGAUGAUAAUCUCAAGACACCUGCGGAGUGUCUGCUCUAUCCCCUUCCACCCUCAGCGGAUGAUAAUCUCAAGACACCUCCCGAGUGUCUGCUCACUCCCCUUCCACCCUCAGCUCCACCCUCAGUGGAUGAUAAUCUCAAGACACCUCCCGAGUGUGUCUGCUCACUCCCCUUCCACCCUCAGCGGAUGAUAAUCUCAAGAAACUAAGGAAGAAUAAAUAAAUAAUAUAAAAAUAAAAUGAA